AAAUAAACCCAAACCCCUCAAACAAUUUCGAACACGAAACAUUCUUCUGAUGCCGGCAUCCCUGCUUGCAGGUGUGAAGGGGGCAGGAAUCAGCGAGGUGUCCUGGGCUGAGUCCCCGGAGUGGGAAGAGGUGGCAGGAAGGGGAUCUGAGGAGGAGAACAGGGGUCCUGGUGGUCUGUGCUUCUUCCCAGACACGGGAGCUGUAGAGGAGACCUCUGCAGCAGAUGCUAGGGGGGCCAGUAGGCCCAGGCAGUCUUGGGACUUGGGUCUGUCCUGCUGUGCAUCCAUAGUGGGUGCUUUAGAAACGGGAGGCCCACCCGAAGUCCCUGUUGCAAGUGAGGACAAAGUGUGGGAAGGCCGUGAGGGUCUGCAGUCCGGGAUGGCCUUGUCCUCAACGUGCAGUGCACUGUUGAUGCGCUGGAAUGCCGUCUCUUUUUCCAGGUGCAGGUCUUCAGCCGUGACCCGGUACCCCAGCUCUAAGGGAGGUGGCAGCAUCAAAGGCUCCCCUCGCCUGCGUGGCAGCAGGGGAAUCUUGCGUCUACGGGGCCUAGAGUCCUGGGAUCUGGGGGAGCCACCCGUUGGGGCGAUUGUCUGCCCUGGUGCUGUAUCUGCCCCCUUUUCACACCGUGUGUGACCCGAAGAGACAGCCUGAGGCCUGUCCUCACUCACUGUCUUUGAGUAACUGAGGGUCAGCUGGCAGCGGGAUGAGGCUGGCCCCCUCCUCUGCUUUAGCCCCGGCAAGCCUCCCGUGGAGCUGUAGGAGCUGGAGAUGGCAUUUCGUUUGGUGCUCGAGCUCGUCCAGGAUGUCUGGGAUGUGUGGUUAUAUCUGAUUUCUGAGCUCUGGGCGUGGAGGUCUGUCUGCAGAGGCCCGGGCCUGGGCACAAAGGGAGAGGGGCCUCCAUUGUCCCGCAGGGGCCAAAAUGCAGACCGUGCAUCCCCGGUGACCUCGGGGACCGUUCUCUGAUCAUCAGGAUUUUCUUGGACUCUGGGGUCCUUGUCCUGCUCAGGCAUCCCUGCCCCGCUCUCCUUGAGGGCCCUCAACACUAUCUUCCCUGGACACAAGUCUGGGGACAGCCGGGUGUUGUGGACCCCAAAGGGGUGACUACCUGCUCCUGGGCCCCACAGAGUCC